GUAGGAGCCUCUCUCCCUACUGCUGCUACACAAGACCCUGAGACUGACCUGCAGGACGAAACCAUGAAGAGCCUGAUCCUUCUUGCCAUCCUGGCCGCCUUAGCGGUAGUAACUUUGUGUUAUGGAGAGUGGCAGAAAGAAGAAAACUUCGGCUUUGAUAUCGUUUCAGUUCUCUCUCUGAACUGGCAUCGUGCCCAGGAAUCACAUGAAAGCAUGGAAUCUUAUGAACUUAAUCCCUUCAUUAACAGGAGAAAUGCAAAUACCUUCAUAUCCCCUCAGCAGAGAUGGAGAGCUAAAGUCCAAGAGAGGAUCCGAGAACGCUCUAAGCCUGUCCACGAGCUCAAUAGGGAAGCCUGUGAUGACUACAGACUUUGCGAACGCUACGCCAUGGUUUAUGGAUACAAUGCUGCCUAUAAUCGCUACUUCAGGAAGCGCCGAGGGACCAAAUGAGACUGAGGGAAGAAAAAAAAUCUCUUUUUUUCUGGAGGCUGGCACCUGAUUUUGUAUCCCCCUGUAGCAGCAUUACAGAAAUACAUAGGCUUAUAUACAAUGCUUCUUUCCUGUAUAUUCUCUUGUCUGGCUGCACCCCUUUUUCCCGCCCCCAGAUUGAUAAGUAAUGAAAGUGCACUGCAGUGAGGGUCAAAGGAGAGUCAACAUAUGUGAUUGUUCCAUAAUAAACUUCUGGUGUGAUACUUUCAUCUUGUAAAUCUGCUUUCUUUUGGGAAGAUAUUGAGAUAUUUAAAUCAUGGCCCACCUUACCCAAAAUAGGAGAUUCUGUUCAUCUCAUAUCUAGUAUUAAUUAGAAAAAUAACUACAUAAAAAGAAGGAAGCUAAGAAGGCACUCACUCAGCCAUAAAUUCUCUAAACCCUCUCUACCUUGGAAUCCGUGAAUGGAAUCUGGUAUGUUUUUUGCAGGAUUUUCCUAUUGUAAAUUGUGGCAAAUACAGGGCUCCCUUCAUUUGCUUUUCAUCUCUUAUGCAUCAAAGUCAAAAACAUUUCUGAAUCAAGAUAAUCUAGAAGAGAAAAAAGGAGGAAAAGGAAAAGAGAAAGCAGAAGGGACAAAUAAAAGCAAUUGGCAAAAACUGUCAAUAAUAGUUUAUACACUUAACUAUAUCAAUAAUCACAUUAUAUGUAAAUAGUCUAAACAAUCCAAUUAUUUUUUACUUCUACUUAUGUUAUAUUUUUACUUCUACAUUUGUUAAAGGUUCCACGCUACAUUUUUACUAUUCUUGCUUUAAAUAAUUUUAAUAAUUUCUUUUAAAGUUUAGAUAAUAAGAAAAUAUCCCGGGCCAGGCACAGUGGCCACACCUGUAAUCUCAGUAGCCAUGACCAUACCAAUGCACUCCAGCCUGUGAAACAGAGUGAGACUCUGUCUCUACAGAAAAAUAAAAAAGAAAAGAAAGAAAAGAUCUCAUAUAUUUACCCAUGUAAUUUUCAUUUCCUGUUUUCUUCAUUCUUCUUUCCAUCUGGUGUCACUUCCUUUCUGCCUGACGACUUCCUUUAACGUUUUUUAUAGUUCAGGUCUGCAGGAUUCUUUAAGUUUUGUAUGCUUGUUUUUAUUCUUGAAAGAUAUUUUCACUGUAUAUUGAAUCCCAAGUUGCCACGUUUCUUUUAAUUAUUUUAAGGUAUUCCACUGAAUUCUAGCUUGCACAAUUUUUCGAUAUAAAAUUUGUUGUAAUUCUUACCUUUGUUCCACUGUGUAUACUGCAUCUUUUAUCUCUGGCU